AGAACUGGGGUUCUUAGAAGUGGUGAUGCAAGAAGUUUCUAGGAAAGGCCGGACACCAGGUGAUUAUUGCUGUUGCUGCCGCCGCUGCUGCUGCUACUGCCGCCGCCGCCGCUGUUGCCGCUGGUGCCGCUGCCGCCGCCGCUGCUCAUGAUCAUUAUUUUACCUUUUAAUUCUUUUUUUUUCCGCUCUUGCCAAAUGCUUUGGCUCCAAGUUUUCUAUGUGUAUCUAUUGAUAUAAAUGUAUAUAUUUAUUUAUUCUAGCUGUCAGGUGUUAAAAUAAAUGCCGAAGAUUAGUCCCACGUCUCUCCCACCAUAGGAUAUAGAUUGUUAUGUAUUUAUUAUUAUUAUUGUUGUCUUUGAGUGAAUCGGCCGGUUUGGGGAGGCUUUUGCCACCCUCCCUUGUGUUGUUUUGGUUUUUGGAAAGGAGGUGGAGGAGAGGAAGGAGGGGAAUUAGGGGGCGGCCGGAGCAGAGAGGACGAGACAGUGCUUGGGGGGUGAUUCGGGCUAGUCUGGGGGCUGUCUGGCCCCAGACCGCGGAGAGGACGCGCGCUCGCGCUCUCGCUCUUUCUGCUGCUGCUUGCGUACGGCUUGUGAUCUCUCUGGAUUCGUGCGGCUGUGUUUUUUCCCUCUUUUCUCGCUUGCAAACUGCUUUCCUUGCUCCGUCGCUCCUGGCCUCCGCUUCCCUCCCUCCUCUUUUUCCUCGCCUCUUCUUCCUUCCCUUCCCCUGUCCUUCUGGGUAACUCCGGGAGGCAAAAAGGGAGGCUGCCCGCUCGCUCGCCCCGCUGGCUCUCUUCCAUCGGCCUCGGUCUUUUAGAUUCCCUGCCUUCGAGCCGAACCGAGAUUUGGAAGGAAAAAAUGCAAGCGAACUCUUUGGGUUUUUGUUUUUGUUUUUUUGGUCAUAAAUCCAGAUGAGAUGAAGUAUCGUGUCUACUAUUUCCUUUCAGAGCCGUGAUCUUCCUAAUGAGAGCCGAGUGUUUUGGUGUUCCCUGCCCCUGUGUUUUGGGGAGCUUGGGGGCGGGGAUGUUGAACACUUUGAAAAUUAUUCUUUCUUGGUUGUAGUCGAGGGAGUCGGGAACCUCCGCGCGCUCUCCCUGCUCAUCCCGAGGAGAGAGACUGAUGGCGGGACAGGGCUUCUUGGGGUGGGUGGGAAAGGGGUGCGCACUGCACCUGCGAUGCCUUUCAGUGUGCGGGGGGACUCAGGGAACCUCGACAGGACAGCCUGGGAGAACGAGAAAGGUGGCGGGAUUUCUGGCCGCUGCGGUGUUUGUAUUUUGGGCGCUGCGUGACUCUGUGUUGGCUCCCAAUGGCUGUUGCCUCCCUUUCCUAAAUUUUAUUUUAUUUUUUCCCAUGGUGCAAGCUCUGUAAAAAGGGAACUGCGGGCCUGAGCGUAGUGGACGCCAGGCUUCAGAUUCCCGAGGUCCUUACCUUGGGCGAGGAGAAAGACGAACAGAGCCCCAGCCCGCGUUCCUUAUGUGCAAGACUCAGGAGGAGAGAAGGGCACUUUGUGGCCGUGGCUGAGGGGACCCGGCGCGGGAGGAGCGGGCGCGGGCGCGAAAGGGAGAUCUUUGUUUUGAGCAAAAUUUUGGACUGUGAAGCAAGGCAUUGGUGAAGACAAAAUGGCCUCGCCGGCUGACAGCUGUAUCCAGUUCACCCGCCAUGCCAGUGAUGUUCUUCUCAACCUUAAUCGUCUCCGGAGUCGAGACAUCUUGACUGAUGUUGUCAUUGUUGUGAGCCGUGAGCAGUUUAGAGCCCAUAAAACGGUCCUCAUGGCCUGCAGUGGCCUGUUCUAUAGCAUCUUUACAGACCAGUUGAAAUGCAACCUUAGUGUGAUCAAUCUAGAUCCUGAGAUCAACCCUGAGGGAUUCUGCAUCCUCCUGGACUUCAUGUACACAUCUCGGCUCAAUUUGCGGGAGGGCAACAUCAUGGCUGUGAUGGCCACGGCUAUGUACCUGCAGAUGGAGCAUGUUGUGGACACUUGCCGGAAGUUUAUUAAGGCCAGUGAAGCAGAGAUGGUUUCUGCCAUCAAGCCUCCUCGUGAAGAGUUCCUCAACAGCCGGAUGCUGAUGCCCCAAGACAUCAUGGCCUAUCGGGGUCGUGAGGUGGUGGAGAACAACCUGCCACUGAGGAGCGCCCCUGGGUGUGAGAGCAGAGCCUUUGCCCCCAGCCUGUACAGUGGCCUGUCCACACCGCCAGCCUCUUAUUCCAUGUACAGCCACCUCCCUGUCAGCAGCCUCCUCUUCUCCGAUGAGGAGUUUCGGGAUGUCCGGAUGCCUGUGGCCAACCCCUUCCCCAAGGAGCGGGCACUCCCAUGUGAUAGUGCCAGGCCAGUCCCUGGUGAGUACAGCCGGCCGACUUUGGAGGUGUCCCCCAAUGUGUGCCACAGCAAUAUCUAUUCACCCAAGGAAACAAUCCCAGAAGAGGCACGAAGUGAUAUGCACUACAGUGUGGCUGAGGGCCUCAAACCUGCUGCCCCCUCAGCCCGAAAUGCCCCCUACUUCCCUUGUGACAAGGCCAGCAAAGAAGAAGAGAGACCCUCCUCGGAAGAUGAGAUUGCCCUGCAUUUCGAGCCCCCCAAUGCACCCCUGAACCGGAAGGGUCUGGUUAGUCCACAGAGCCCCCAGAAAUCUGACUGCCAGCCCAACUCGCCCACAGAGUCCUGCAGCAGUAAGAAUGCCUGCAUCCUCCAGGCUUCUGGCUCCCCUCCAGCCAAGAGCCCCACUGACCCCAAAGCCUGCAACUGGAAGAAAUACAAGUUCAUCGUGCUCAACAGCCUCAACCAGAAUGCCAAACCAGAGGGGCCUGAGCAGGCUGAGCUGGGCCGCCUUUCCCCACGAGCCUACACGGCCCCACCUGCCUGCCAGCCACCCAUGGAGCCUGAGAACCUUGACCUCCAGUCCCCAACCAAGCUGAGUGCCAGCGGGGAGGACUCCACCAUCCCACAAGCCAGCCGGCUCAAUAACAUCGUUAACAGGUCCAUGACGGGCUCUCCCCGCAGCAGCAGCGAGAGCCACUCACCACUCUACAUGCACCCCCCGAAGUGCACGUCCUGCGGCUCUCAGUCCCCACAGCAUGCAGAGAUGUGCCUCCACACCGCUGGCCCCACGUUCCCUGAGGAGAUGGGAGAGACCCAGUCUGAGUACUCAGAUUCUAGCUGUGAGAACGGGGCCUUCUUCUGCAAUGAGUGUGACUGCCGCUUCUCUGAGGAGGCCUCACUCAAGAGGCACACGCUGCAGACCCACAGUGACAAACCCUACAAGUGUGACCGCUGCCAGGCCUCCUUCCGCUACAAGGGCAACCUCGCCAGCCACAAGACCGUCCAUACCGGUGAGAAACCCUAUCGUUGCAACAUCUGUGGGGCCCAGUUCAACCGGCCAGCCAACCUGAAAACCCACACUCGAAUUCACUCUGGAGAGAAGCCCUACAAAUGCGAAACCUGCGGAGCCAGAUUUGUACAGGUGGCCCACCUCCGUGCCCAUGUGCUUAUCCACACUGGUGAGAAGCCCUAUCCCUGUGAAAUCUGUGGCACCCGUUUCCGGCACCUUCAGACUCUGAAGAGCCACCUGCGAAUCCACACAGGAGAGAAACCUUACCAUUGUGAGAAGUGUAACCUGCAUUUCCGUCACAAAAGCCAGCUGCGACUUCACUUGCGCCAGAAGCAUGGCGCCAUCACCAACACCAAGGUGCAAUACCGCGUGUCAGCCACUGACCUGCCUCCGGAGCUCCCCAAAGCCUGCUGAAGCAUGGAGUGUUGAUGCUUUCGUCUCCAGCCCCUUCUCAGAAUCUACCCAAAGGAUACUGUAACACUUUACAAUGUUCAUCCCAUGAUGUAGUGCCUCUUUCAUCCACUAGUGCAAAUCAUAGCUGGGGGUUGGGGGUGGUGGGGGUCGGGGCCUGGGGGACUGGGAGCCGCAGCAGCUCCCCCUCCCCCACUGCCAUAAAACAUUAAGAAAAUCAUAUUGCUUCUUCUCCUAUGUGUAAGGUGAACCAUGUCAGCAAAAAGCAAAAUCAUUUUAUAUGUCAAAGCAGGGGAGUAUGCAAAAGUUCUGACUUGACUUUAGUCUGCAAAAUGAGGAAUGUAUAUGUUUUGUGGGAACAGAUGUUUCUUUUGUAUGUAAAUGUGCAUUCUUUUAAAAGACAAGACUUCAGUAUGUUGUCAAAGAGAGGGCUUUAAUUUUUUUAACCAAAGGUGAAGGAAUAUAUGGCAGAGUUGUAAAUAUAUAAAUAUAUAUAUAUAUAAAAUAAAUAUAUAUAAACCUAAAAAAGAUAUAUUAAAAAUAUAAAACUGCGUUAAAGGCUCGAUUUUGUAUCUGCAGGCAGACACGGAUCUGAGAAUCUUUAUUGAGAAAGAGCACUUAAGAGAAUAUUUUAAGUAUUGCAUCUGUAUAAGUAAGAAAAUAUUUUGUCUAAAAUGCCUCAGUGUAUUUGUAUUUUUUUGCAAGUGAAGGUUUACAAUUUACAAAGUGUGUAUUAAAAAAAACAAAAAGAACAAAAAAAUCUGCAGAAGGAAAAAUGUGUAAUUUUGUUCUAGUUUUCAGUUUGUAUAUACCCGUACAACGUGUCCUCACGGUGCCUUUUUUCACGGAAGUUUUCAAUGAUGGGCGAGCGUGCACCAUCCCUUUUUGAAGUGUAGGCAGACACAGGGACUUGAAGUUGUUACUAACUAAACUCUCUUUGGGAAUGUUUGUCUCAUCCCAUUCUGCGUCAUGCUUGUGUUAUAACUACUCCGGAGACAGGGUUUGGCUGUGUCUAAACUGCAUUACCGCGUUGUAAAAUAUAGCUGUACAAAUAUAAGAAUAAAAUGUUGAAAAGUCAAACUGG